ACUCGCUCGCUCCCCCCGCCAGCGGAAGCGUCCGCGAAGCACAAUGCAGCACUGAGCCGCGGUGGAGGUUGCAGCGCCACGGCCGCCGCAGCACCGGCCGGGGCUGGGUGGAGGUGGCCGCGGGGACCCCGGGGGCGCGGAGCGAGGGAAACGGACUCGGCGGCGCCGGCAUGAGGAGCUGAGCGUCUCGGGCGAGGCGGGCUGACGGCAGCACCAUGCAGGCGGCAGUGGCUGUGUCCGUGCCCUUCUUGCUGCUCUGUGUCCUGGGGACCUGCCCUCCGGCGCGCUGCGGCCAGGCAGGAGACGCCUCAUUGAUGGAGCUAGAGAAGAGGAAGGAAAACCGCUUCGUGGAGCGCCAGAGCAUCGUGCCACUGCGCCUCAUCUACCGCUCGGGCGGCGAAGACGAAAGUCGGCACGACGCGCUCGACACGCGGGUGCGGGGCGACCUCGGUGGCCCGCAGUUGACUCAUGUUGACCAAGCAAGCUUCCAGGUUGAUGCCUUUGGAACGUCAUUCAUUCUCGAUGUCGUGCUAAAUCAUGAUUUGCUGUCCUCUGAAUACAUAGAGAGACACAUUGAACAUGGAGGCAAGACUGUGGAAGUUAAAGGAGGAGAGCACUGUUACUACCAGGGCCAUAUCCGAGGAAACCCUGACUCAUUUGUUGCAUUGUCAACAUGCCACGGACUUCAUGGGAUGUUCUAUGACGGGAACCACACAUAUCUCAUUGAGCCAGAAGAAAAUGACACUACUCAAGAGGAUUUCCAUUUUCAUUCAGUUUACAAAUCCAGACUGUUUGAAUUUUCCUUGGAUGAUCUUCCAUCUGAAUUUCAGCAAGUAAACAUUACUCCAUCAAAAUUUAUUUUGAAGCCAAGACCAAAAAGGAGUAAACGGCAGCUUCGUCGAUAUCCUCGUAAUGUAGAAGAAGAAACCAAAUACAUUGAACUGAUGAUUGUGAAUGAUCACCUUAUGUUUAAAAAACAUCGGCUUUCCGUUGUACAUACCAAUACCUAUGCGAAAUCUGUGGUGAACAUGGCAGAUUUAAUAUAUAAAGACCAACUUAAGACCAGGAUAGUAUUGGUUGCUAUGGAAACCUGGGCGACUGACAACAAGUUUGCCAUAUCUGAAAAUCCAUUGAUCACCCUACGUGAGUUUAUGAAAUACAGGAGGGAUUUUAUCAAAGAGAAAAGUGAUGCAGUUCACCUUUUUUCGGGAAGUCAAUUUGAGAGUAGCCGGAGCGGGGCAGCUUAUAUUGGUGGGAUUUGCUCGUUGCUGAAAGGAGGAGGCGUGAAUGAAUUUGGGAAAACUGAUUUAAUGGCUGUUACACUUGCCCAGUCAUUAGCCCAUAAUAUUGGUAUUAUCUCAGACAAAAGAAAGUUAGCAAGUGGUGAAUGUAAAUGCGAGGACACGUGGUCCGGGUGCAUAAUGGGAGACACUGGCUAUUAUCUUCCUAAAAAGUUCACCCAGUGUAAUAUUGAAGAGUAUCAUGACUUCCUGAAUAGUGGAGGUGGUGCCUGCCUUUUCAACAAACCUUCUAAGCUUCUUGAUCCUCCUGAGUGUGGCAAUGGCUUCAUUGAAACUGGAGAGGAGUGUGAUUGUGGAACCCCGGCCGAAUGUGUCCUUGAAGGAGCAGAGUGUUGUAAGAAAUGCACCUUGACUCAAGACUCUCAAUGCAGUGACGGUCUUUGCUGUAAAAAGUGCAAGUUUCAGCCUAUGGGCACUGUGUGCCGAGAAGCAGUAAAUGAUUGUGAUAUUCGUGAAACGUGCUCAGGAAAUUCAAGCCAGUGUGCCCCUAAUAUUCAUAAAAUGGAUGGAUAUUCAUGUGAUGGUGUUCAGGGAAUUUGCUUUGGAGGAAGAUGCAAAACCAGAGAUAGACAAUGCAAAUACAUUUGGGGGCAAAAGGUGACAGCAUCAGACAAAUAUUGCUAUGAGAAACUGAAUAUUGAAGGGACGGAGAAGGGUAACUGUGGGAAAGACAAAGACACAUGGAUACAGUGCAACAAACGGGAUGUGCUUUGUGGUUACCUUUUGUGUACCAAUAUUGGCAAUAUCCCAAGGCUUGGAGAACUCGAUGGUGAAAUCACAUCUACUUUAGUUGUGCAGCAAGGAAGAACAUUAAACUGCAGUGGUGGGCAUGUUAAGCUUGAAGAAGAUGUAGAUCUUGGCUAUGUGGAAGAUGGGACACCUUGUGGUCCCCAAAUGAUGUGCUUAGAACACAGGUGUCUUCCUGUGGCUUCUUUCAACUUUAGUACUUGCUUGAGCAGUAAAGAAGGCACUAUUUGCUCAGGAAAUGGAGUUUGCAGUAAUGAGCUGAAGUGUGUGUGUAACAGACACUGGAUAGGUUCUGAUUGCAACACUUACUUCCCUCACAAUGAUGAUGCAAAGACUGGUAUCACUCUGUCUGGCAAUGGUGUUGCUGGCACCAAUAUCAUAAUAGGCAUAAUUGCUGGCACCAUUUUAGUGCUGGCCCUCAUAUUAGGAAUAACUGCGUGGGGUUAUAAAAACUAUCGAGAACAGAGACAGUUACCCCAGGGAGAUUAUGUAAAAAAGCCUGGAGAUGGUGACUCUUUUUAUAGCGACAUUCCUCCCGGAGUCAGCACAAACUCAGCAUCUAGUUCUAAGAAGAGGUCUGCUUUUCUGUCGCAUUUUCAGAUUUCUACCUGUUCCAUCACACAUUAUUCCAUUAGUCAGAACAUUUCAUUAUUUUGCAGCAGGUCAAAUGGGCUCUCUCAUUCUUGGAGUGAAAGGAUUCCAGACACAAAACAUAUUUCAGACAUCUGUGAAAAUGGGCGACCUCGAAGUAACUCUUGGCAAGGUAACCUGGGAGGCAACAAAAAGAAAAUCAGAGGCAAAAGAUUUAGACCUCGGUCUAAUUCAACUGAGAGGGAGCCCCAAGCACCUGAGCCUGGGCACUCCCUCGCCCAGACAGUCCCAUCCCAAGGCAUAAGCCCAGGGGGCUCUGACAGCCCCCAGACAGGGAGUCUGGAUCACAGGUAUUUAAACCCAUGGUUCAAAAGAGACUAUAAUGUAGCUAAGUGGGUAGAAGAUGUGAAUAAAAACACUGAAGGACCAUACUUUAGGACUUUAUCUCCUGCCAAGUCUCCUUCUUCAUCAACUGGGUCUAUUGCCUCCAGCAGAAAAUACCCUUACCCAAUGCCUCCACUUCCUGAUGAGGACAAGAAAGUGAACCGACAAAGUGCCAGGCUAUGGGAGACAUCCAUUUAAGAUCAACUGUUUACAUGUGAUACAUCGAAAACUGUUUACUUCAACUUUUAUAGAAACCCAGGCUCAUGGAAUCACUGCAAAUCUAUCUGCUCUUCAGACAAUACGAAGACCCUCUGAGAUGCUACAGAGGAGAGGAAGCGGAGUUUCACAUCUGGUUACCAUUUUCUUUUUGUCAUUGGCUUAGGAUUUAACUAACCAUGAAAAGAACUACUGAAAUAUUACACUAUAACAUGGAACAAUAAAGGUACUGGUAUGUUAAUGGAUAAUCCGCAUGACAGAUAAUAUGUAGAAAUAUUCAUAAAGUUAACUCACAUGACCCAAAUGUAGCAAGUUUCCUAAGGUACAAUAGUGGAUUCAGAACUUGACGUUCUGAGGCACAUCCUCACUGUAAACAGUAAUGCUAUAUGCAUGAAGCUUCUGUUUAUUGUUUUCCAUAUUUAAGGAAACAACAUCCCAUAAUAGAAAUGAGCAUGCAGGGCUAAGGCAUAUAGGAUUUUUCUGCAGGACUUUAAAGCUUUGAAAGGCCAAUAUCCCAUAGGCUAACUUUAAACAUGUAUUUUUAUUUUUGUUUUGUUUUUUACUUUUCAUAUUUAUAUUAGCAUACAAGGACAAUUGUAUAUAUGUAACAUUUUUAAAAUUUUAAAAAAAUGCAGCUGUUACACACAAGUGUAUUUUGCCAAAUGCCUAAAAAUUCCGUCACAAUCACAUCAUCGUCAUCCAUCCAGUGAUCUUCAAAGACUAUAAGCAGGUAAUGUAAAUAUAGUGGUCAAUGCUGUAAAUGUGUCUCUCCAUAAUUCGUAUUUGUCCAAAACAUGUGAUAUCCCUUUAACCUGUGCACAGUCUGGAGGCAGUUUUAUUGAGUGAGUAGUUGAGUGAGAGAACAAAAUGCCCAGCAAAACUUCUGGCCUCCACAGUUUGCUGAUGCAGGAGCCCACUCUGCUGCCGAUGGGCUGCUCCCUGGAAAUCAUCUAUCCCAUCCGUCCAUCCCAUCUCAUCCCAGUGAGCCAGCCCCUCAGCAGUGUGUGCUGCUGAGAUUAAGCAAGUGCACCAAAGACACAUGAGACAACGUACUGCCAGUGAGCUGGUAGCUUCUGGUUUGCCAAUACUCUAACCCUUUGUGGCCUGAAGUUUUGUUCCUUGGCAAAACUUUGUAGUCACCCUUAUCUGUGAAAUGAAUGACUUGUUUUAACAAAAACAACUUUGACACUGUUGAUUAAGAAUAUUUGUCAUCACUGGGAUGUGAAUCCCAACAAGUCAUUCUGCACUGACUCUGAAGCAAGAUGACGGAAGAUUCUACUGUUUGAGUUGAGCAGCUUCAACCAUUCAUAAAGGGUUAAGUUAGAUCUAAACCACAGAGAUGCAGCAUCUGCGAAGUUACACUAACAGCUGGUGGGGGAAAGAAUCUGAUGCUUUGAAACAUAUAUUUUUAAUCCAUAGGAAAAUAAGAUUCUAUUUUAAAAGACCCUUCUUUAAAACCAAAGUUUGAUAGCUGUUAUAAUGGCAGAUCUGUCAUUCCAAAAGAAAGCUAGCUACCCUAGUGAGGCUGGAGAUUGAUGGGCUCAAUCACAUGGUCUGCUCUGAAGUAUACUUCUGAUUUCCUCAUUUGCUGUGUGUUCUUAAGAGGAAUGGAAUCUGCAGACAGGUUUUCAGAUAUACUCUCUUAAAUUUGAUCCUCUCCCAUAGUAUCCAUGGACAAAAUCCAUAUCAUCUUCAUAUGUAAUCAAUUUGAUUACAUAUCAUGCCCAAACUGAAGGGCCGAGUUAGAAGGCAGCAUUUUAUACUGUGUGUUUAUGUCUUCUGUAAUGGACCUCUCUUUUGAAAGUCUUUGAAAUGUUUGGAAAGCAAUUUAAUGAUCCAAAAUUACAUAAUGUAAAACAGCAUUUUUCAUGACAGGAAGGGAUGUGAUUGUUGAUAUGACCAUAAAGCGAUCCAUCAGGCCAAGGUUUGGGUGAGUGUUGGGCAGUGUUGCCACAUAGCUCAAGCCAAGAACAGAAGGGCAGACAGAUUGAAAGAUGUAGCAAAUAAAGUGACUUUUUACCAAGAUCACUGUAACGUGCACUGAAUGUUUCCUGGUACUGAGUGUACAAAAGGCUAAUGCUAUAAGGUUUAUUUUGACUAUAAAAGAGUUUAUAGAUUUGAAUAUAAGGUGCCUCAUGUAAAUAUGCUUCCUAGUUACAGGUACACAAACUCUAAUUUGAAAGAAUCCACAAAUGGCUAGCUGAGAAGUUAACAGAUCUCUAUCAUUCGUCUGUGUGUCUUUCUUCCCUCACCUAUUUUUACAUGAAAUUAUUAUUUCAAAUGAAAAUCAUGAUCAUGUGCCUUUUGGGAGACAUGGUUUCUCUAGAGGUAUAUAGUUUGUAAUUACCCGCCUUGGUAAUAACCUUCCUGUGGAACUGACUAAAAAUUUUUGUUUUAUUUGUAGAGAUUAUGAUUUGAGGUAUACAGUAACUUUAAUGUUCUAUUCUUGGAAUCUACUCUAUCUCCCAUGUUUAAACAUUCUUAGAGCCAUUUGUGGGAUUCAUUGACAAAUUUAUAGUCUCAAGGGAGAGUUUCAAGAAGUAUCUAUAUGUAUACUCAUGGUUGGGGUUCUAGAGGCAUUACAUCUAAAUAUUUAUGACUUUUCAUCCACCGAGGUAGGUAGCAUUAAAUAUACAAGCACAGCAUUAUUUCUCUUUAAAUAUCUAUUUUGGAGAGAAACUUUGAGGCCGUAUCACAGUUUAUAUCAUGCAACUAAUAUUUAUAUUUCCCAAUCCACUACAAAAUCAUUGCUAAGCAGAAGAGAGCAGUUAUUUGGCCUUUAUGUUCCAUUGUAUGCCUUUUUCCCCUCUUCCAGUUUUAUGCAUUGAUAAGACUACAGAUUGGCACCCUGCUGCCUGAGAAGUUCCAUUUAUCCAUAGUCAUUGCAGUGCAGUAAACCCUGAUUUAAAGGAACAUUUAAGUCUCUCCAGUAAGUGUGAACAGGAAGGCAUGGGAUAGAAGAGAGUCCUUAUGGAGUGGACUGGCCACAUGAACUGUCCUCCAGCCACUCUUUAUUUAGAUGGGAAGUGGCAUGGUCCUCUGAACGCUGCAGGCUGGAAAUGAUCCCCAGGGCACAUGCAAUCUGUGGAAAGGAAUACAUCGGACAGUGCAACAUGGUGAGGGCUUUCAAUUUGCUGUGGUUGCUGUAUUUUUAACAAGACACCCGGAGCUUCGAUUAGGAAUAACCUAUCAUUAGAGUUGUUCCUUUAAAAAAUGUUGAUGAAUAAAGCAAAUGUGGGUUUAAAAUGCCAACUUAUUUUUCACUUUGAUAUUGGUGCUUUAUUAAGUGAUACCAUAGUUUCUCUCUCUUUUCCCUGUUACUUUAAAAAGAAUUUUAAAAUUGUGUUUGUAUAUAAGGUCAGUCUGGCAUAGAAUUUCUGAAAGUAACAUUAAUAGGAUUUCUAAAGAAGUUGUCAGAAAGACAAAAUUGGAUAUUCUCUGCACUUUCAGAGAAGGACUAUUUAUGUUUGAAUUUCAUAACAGGCUUACAUUUCUUUUCUAUUGAUUCCCUUGCAUAUCUACAUAAUUUAAUCCUGUCUAUUGUCCCAGAUCUCUUGUGGCUACUUUACCUGUUACCUUUUUUGGGAUUUUGUUCUUUAUGUUUUACAGUUACCUUCGGACCAGAAGAUAUAUGGUAUUUUUAUUCACUUUUUUCAGUGUUUUAAAAUAAGGUUUGUUCAUUUAUUCAUUUUAUCCAUUCAUUUCCUAUUGUCGUAUAGUUCUAACCAUAUAUAUAGUACUUUAAAUAUUUUCUUAUGUUAUUAUUUAACACAAUAAUAAAUUCUUAUCUAAAGAAAAGAUUAUUUUACUUUAUUUUACUUAAAGGAAAGAGAAUUUAUUGGCAGGAUAUUGAGUAGCUUGUAGAGUAUAUGGAAGGGGAGAGCCAAGUUAGGAACUGGCAGGAGCGAGGAGGGACAAGACAGCUGCCUGCACAGUCUGAUAGGACACAUCUGGCUGCUGCCACUGGAUGCCCACAUGGGCAGCGUGUUGUAAAUAUCACCCUACCAGUUGGUAAGUUGGCAUGAAUUUUCCAUGAAACACUUGACUGCCAUUUGCAGCAUCAUAUCUACUUUUUAUGCACCUAAUUAUAUUUUUCCUUUCACUUUUAUGUUUUUUUCUAAAACUGCCACCUAAAUACCUUUCCACUCCGUUAAAUGUAUGGAGUCAAGAUAAAUUUCUCAUUCUUGCUCUACAGUUUAAGAUGUAUAAGAAGUAAACACUUCCGUGGAAUAGGGCUUAAUUUGGGGCUCAAAUGUUUUGUUUUCCUCCUGAGAUGUUUUUGAAUGGAUAAGACUACUCUGGUUUUGGAUGCAGCAACUUUUCUCCUGGCAUGGAAGAACUAAGGACUUUGAUAAACAGUUUCCCAUUGAUAGUAUAAUAUAAUGAGGGGCCCAGUCUGCUCUUGUGAAAAUUGGCUGAGCGGCAGCAGCCCAUCCCAGCUGUGUGUGAGUAGCCCCGCUGUUAAAAGUACACCUGCUGGGAAUUGUUGGCACAUGCUCAUAGCAUAUGCUCUGUGGGGGAGGUGCUUUUAAUUCCAAGAGGAGCUUUUCUCCCACAUCUGCGGAUGCAGAACAAAGAUGCAGCAGGACUUUAGAAAACAGGAGUGUUUCUACUGACAUUUUAUUCAUUGCUUUGUUAGUCCCGCAAAUGGAGCAACUUCUGGUUGUUUGUAAGCAGAAAAACAAAACAUUCAAAACCAAAAACCUAAUUAGUACUUUUGUCCUUUAUAUCCCUAGGAUGCUCUAGGGAGUAGAGGUGGCAGGCAUCUUUAUCUUCACCCACUGGCACAUUAGCAGCUUAUGCAACUUAGGAAGUCACUGGGAGAUGAGUCCUAAAAGCCUGAAUUUCAGGAUGGGGAGGAGAUAAGAAGCAGAGAACUUUGGGAGACCAUGGGGCAUUUAGUCCUGGCAUAGACACAGAAUGGAUAUUCACAGGAAGAUUCCUGAGGCCAGAUAUGCAGGAGAGCACACAUUGUCACAAGGGGUGUGGUGGGAAGAGAGGUGCUGGAUGCCUAAGACAGACUUCUGUGCUUGGCAGAUUGACUGAGUGUUGACUCUGAAUACUUUGUGGUCCAGUCCAUAAUAGGCCAGUCACUCCUGCCUGAUGCAUCCCUGUUGCACUGUUCAUAAAACCUGUAUCAUAUGGGGAAGCUUCAAGGCUGGCAGGCUUUUCAUCAAGUAAUCAUCAUUCCAUGUUCCUACGUAUCCUUGAAAUCAAAACCAGGCAAUAUGUGUGUUUUUGGUUUUGUUUUACAAAAAGGCAUACAAUGAGACGAAUUCUUAAGAUAAUGCACAUACAGAAUCAUCAAUAAAGUUUCAAAGAGUUUAUGAAGAAAAGGUAUUUUCCUUUCUUGUAAAAAAUGUUAUAUAUAUAUAAUAUUCUGAUCUGCAUUCACCUUAGGGCUUAGCCUCUUAUUUUAUGAAUUUUCAGGCUGUGAUUUGUGUUGGAUGGCUAAGCUCUAAAAUAAUGCAAAUAGCCCCAAUCUUUAAAUAUAGCGGUGCUAAGUUGAACAAGUAACACAAUACAGAAAAUGCUGAUAUGAAUACUUAGUAAUAAUACAAAAGUUCCUGCUAAAUUAUAUAUGUGUAUCACUGCCUGACUAGAAACCCCACUUUUCUUUUCUAAUCCAGCACAAAAUCAAACUCUGAUUCUACAACCAGUCUUUUUAAAGGGCAAAAAUGACUCAACACCUUUGUUUUGUAUGGAAAACUUUUUUUUUUACACUAACUGCAAAACUGCUUUAAAAAAAGGCUUAUUCAGGAUAGAUAAGCAUGUACUCCUUUUUUAACUUGCUGGAAGACUUGCCCCUCCAAACUAGCACCCCCAAAAGACAACUUCUUUCAGAAACGGGGUGUUUUACCUAAACAUAGUAGCUUACAUGUUAGCCAGCAGUAGGUCGGCACUAGUGUUUUCCACGGUUAUCACCUUUGACAGGUGAUGUGCAUCUAUAGAUAGUGGAAGCCACCCCAUGAGGAGGUGUUAAUAGCAGCAUGGUUUCACUUUUGGUAAUCAGGUAAUCAUGUGUAUAUACUUAGAUUCGCAUUAUUUUAACAUUUCUCUGCUACUCUGCACUUCAGGUUCGUUAAGCUAUUUUAAUAAUUACUGGGGUUAUGGCAAACACCAAUGGAAAUGUAUAUGGCAACUGCUUUCCUGAGCAAGUGUGAUUUGUUUUAUGGCUGUUCAAGUUAUAAAAUUGUUCUUACAUUGUAGGUAAACAAAAUCUUGAUGUUUUUAAAGGUCACUGUAACUUAAGGUUCAAAUUUCUGGCACAGUUUUAUUAGUAUUCACUUCGGAAGCUAAUAAGAUACCAUGGUUUUCUAUGUUACUCCCAUUGUAACAUUAGUAAAGUGACUUUCAAUAAAAGAUUUAUGUUAUUUUGA